CCUAGUUUCUAAGGAUCAUGUCUGCGAGCCAGGAUUCCCGAUCCAGAGACAAUGGCCCCGAUGGGAUGGAGCCCGAAGGCGUCAUCGAGAGUAACUGGAAUGAGAUUGUUGACAGCUUUGAUGACAUGAACCUCUCGGAGUCCCUUCUCCGUGGCAUCUACGCGUAUGGUUUUGAGAAGCCCUCUGCCAUCCAGCAGCGAGCCAUUCUACCUUGUAUCAAGGGUUAUGAUGUGAUUGCUCAAGCCCAAUCUGGGACUGGGAAAACGGCCACAUUUGCCAUAUCGAUUCUGCAGCAGAUUGAAUUAGAUCUAAAAGCCACCCAGGCCUUGGUCCUAGCACCCACUCGAGAAUUGGCUCAGCAGAUACAGAAGGUGGUCAUGGCACUAGGAGACUACAUGGGCGCCUCCUGUCACGCCUGUAUCGGGGGCACCAACGUGCGUGCUGAGGUGCAGAAACUGCAGAUGGAAGCUCCCCACAUCAUCGUGGGUACCCCUGGCCGUGUGUUUGAUAUGCUUAACCGGAGAUACCUGUCCCCCAAAUACAUCAAGAUGUUUGUACUGGAUGAAGCUGACGAAAUGUUAAGCCGUGGAUUCAAGGACCAGAUCUAUGACAUAUUCCAAAAGCUCAACAGCAACACCCAGGUAGUUUUGCUGUCAGCCACAAUGCCUUCUGAUGUGCUUGAGGUGACCAAGAAGUUCAUGAGGGACCCCAUUCGGAUUCUUGUCAAGAAGGAAGAGUUGACCCUGGAGGGUAUCCGCCAGUUCUACAUCAACGUGGAACGAGAGGAGUGGAAGCUGGACACACUAUGUGACUUGUAUGAAACCCUGACCAUCACCCAGGCAGUCAUCUUCAUCAACACCCGGAGGAAGGUGGACUGGCUCACCGAGAAGAUGCAUGCUCGAGAUUUCACUGUAUCCGCCAUGCAUGGAGAUAUGGACCAAAAGGAACGAGACGUGAUUAUGAGGGAGUUUCGUUCUGGCUCUAGCAGAGUUUUGAUUACCACUGACCUGCUGGCCAGAGGCAUUGAUGUGCAGCAGGUUUCUUUAGUCAUCAACUAUGACCUUCCCACCAACAGGGAAAACUAUAUCCACAGAAUCGGUCGAGGUGGACGGUUUGGCCGUAAAGGUGUGGCUAUUAACAUGGUGACAGAAGAAGACAAGAGGACUCUUCGAGACAUUGAGACCUUCUACAACACCUCCAUUGAGGAAAUGCCCCUCAAUGUUGCUGACCUCAUCUGAGGGGCUGUCCUGCCACCCAGCCCCAGCCAGGGCUCAAUCUCUGGGGGCUGAGGAGCAGCAGGAGGGGGGAGGGAAGGGAGCCAAGGGAUGGACAUCUUGUCAUUUUUUUUCUUUGAAUAAAUGUCACUUUUUGAGGCAAAAGAAGGAACCGUGAACAUUUUAGACACCCUUUUCUUUGGGGUAGGCUCUUGCCCCAGGCGCCGGCUCUUCUCCCAAAAAAAAAAAAAAAACACUAAUCCAUUUCCCUAACCUAGUAACCUCCAGAUCCCAGAGGCUCUCCUCACCUCAGCUGAGCUCCUUUGAAAGUGAUUCAAGGGACUAUGUCACUCAGCCUCAUUUGCUGGACCAAAUCUGGAGGGAGAACCCCUAAAACCCCUAAGUGAGGUUGCCCAGGGGGUUGUCCCCAGGUGGGGGGAAGCAGGGGAGAGAAAAUGGUAGCCAUUUUUACAUUGUUUUGUAUAGUAUUUAUUGAUUCAGGAAACAAACACAAAAUUCUGAAUAAAAUGACUUGGAAACUGCC